GUAUUCAGCGGCGACAGCGGCGACUGCGGCGGCCGCGGGAGGGCAUCCCGUUGGGGAUCCUUCCGCACACUGAAGAGUACGUCUUCGGGUCUACCCCUAAUCACAUAAUGGCUGUGUUUAAUCAGAAGUCUGUCUCGGAUAUGAUUAAAGAGUUUCGAAAAAAUUGGCGUGCUCUUUGUAACUCUGAGAGAACUACUCUAUGUGGUGCAGACUCCAUGCUCUUGGCAUUGCAGCUUUCUAUGGCGGAGAACAACAAACAGUGUCCUAGUGUGGCUUUGGAAUCCGGGUCAUGGUUGUUUCAUAAAAUGAGUUUGGAAGUAUUCCCUUUUCAUUUUUUUGGAAGAGUUCUUAGUGCAUACAGAACAUUCGUCAAGAUAGAUCAUAUGUUAGCCCACAAAACAAGUCUUAACAAAUUUAAGAAGAUUGAAAUCAUACUGAGUAUCUUUUCUGAUUACAGUGGUAUGAAACUAGAAAUCUGUAACAGGAAGAAUUUGGAAAAUUAACAAACACGUGGAAAUUAACCAACGGUUCGAAGAAGAAAUUAAAAGGAAAUUUAAAAAAACCUUAAAAAAUAUGGAAGUACAACAUACCACAACUUAUGGGAUAGAGCAAAAGCAAUUCUAAGAGGAAAGCUUAUAGCAAUAAACACCUACAUUGAAAGAAAAAAAGAUCUUUAAUAAACUUAACAUUACACCAAAAGAAACUAGGAAAAGAACACACUAAGCCCAAACUUAGCAGAAGGAAGAGAAUAAUAAAGAUGAGAGCAGAAAUAAAUGAAAUAGAGACUAAAAAAACAAUAGCAAAGAUCAAUGAAGCUAAGAGUUGGCUUUUUGAAAAGAUAAACAAAAUCAACAAACCUUUAGGUAAAAGUAAGAAAAAAGAGAAGCCUCAAAAAAAAAAAAAAAGAAAUGAAAAAGGAUACAUUAUAACUAAUACCACAGAAAUAAAACAGGUCAUAAAAGACUACUAUGAACAAUUUGUAUGCCAACAAAUUGGAUAACCUAGAAGAAAUGGAUAAAUUCCUUGACACGUACUAUCUACCAAGACUACAUCAUGAAGAAAUAGGAACUCUGAAUAGACCAAUAAGAAAUAAGGACAUUGAAUCAGUAAUAAAAAGUCUUUUAUUAAAGAAAAGCCCAGGACCUGAUGGCUUUACUGCUGAAUUCUACCAAACAUUUAAAGAACUAAUACCAAUCCUUCUCAAACUCUUCCAAAAGCAUGCAGAAGGGGGAACACUUUCCAGCUCAUUUUAUGAAGCCAGUAGGAGAGACGGGGUUUCACCAUGUUAGCCAGGAUGGUCUCGAUCUCCUGACUUCGUGAUCCACCCGCCUCGGCCUCCCAAAGUGCUAAAAUUACAGGCGUGAACCACCACCACAGUGGAGAAUUUACAGUCUCUCUCAGUGAUGUUUUAUUGACAUGGAAAUACUUGCUCCAUGAGAAAUUGAACUUACCAGUUGAAAACAUGGACGUGACUGACCAUUAUGAGGACGUUAGGAAGAUUUAUGAUGAUUUCUUGAAGAACAGUAAUAUGUUAGAUCUGAUUGAUGUUUAUCAAAAAUGUAGGGCUUUGACUUCUAAUUGUGAAAAUUAUAACACAGUAUCUCCUAGUCAACUACUGGAUUUUCUGUCUGGCAAACAGUAUGCAGUAGGUGAUGAAACUGAUCUUUCUAUACCAACAUCACCAACAAGUAAAUACAACCGUGAUAAUGAAAAGGUGCAGCUGCUAGCAAGGAAAAUUAUCUUUUCAUAUUUAAAUCUGCUAGUGAAUUCAAAGAAUGACCUGGCUGUGGCUUAUAUUCUCAAUAUUCCUGAUAGAGGACUAGGAAGAGAAGCCUUCACUGAUUUGAAACAUGCUGCUCGAGAGAAACAAAUGUCUAUCUUUUUGGUGGCCACGUCUUUUAUUAGAACAAUAGAGCUUGGAGGGAAAGGAUAUGCACCACCACCAUCAGAUCCUUUAAGGACACAUGUAAAGGGAUUGUCUAAUUUUAUUAAUUUCAUUGACAAAUUAGAUGAGAUUCUUGGAGAAAUACCAAACCCAAGGUCUCCCACACAGGUGAAUAAUUCGAUAAAACCCCUAAGAGAACGCAUCUGUGUGUCAAUGCAAGAGAAAAAAAUUAAGAUGAAGCAAACUUUAAUUAGAUCCCAAUUUGCUUGUACUUAUAAAGAUGACUACAUGAUAAGCAAGGAUAAUUGGAAUAAUGUUAAUUUAGCAUCAAAGCCUUUGUGUGUUCUUUACAUGGAAAAUGACCUUUCUGAGGGUGUAAAUCCAUCUGUUGGAAGAUCAACAAUUGGAACGAGUUUUGGAAAUGUUCAUCUGGACAGAAGUAAAAAUGAAAAAGUAUCAAGAAAAUCAACCAGUCAGACAGGAAAUAAAAGCUCAAAAAGGAAACAGGUGGAUUUGGAUGGUGAAAAUAUUCUCUGUGAUAAUAGAAAUGAACCACCUCAACAUAAAAAUGCUAAAAUACCUAAGAAAUCAAAUGAUUCACAGAAUAGAUUGUACGGCAAACUAGCUAAAGUAGCAAAAAGUAAUAAAUGUACUGCCAAGGACAAGUUGAUUUCUGGCCAGGCAAAGUUAACUCAGUUUUUUAGACUAUAAAUUUGUGUCUUAUAUGCUUUAGGUUUAUGUAUCUAUAAACCAUUCACCAAAGACAUGCUUAAUUUUUAAGAGAUCAAGGUGUAAAUUAUGAUGAUUUAUUAUUUUGGUCUACAGUGUAUGUAAGGUUAGUAUGUUAAGCAUUGUUUAAAAAUACUAGUAAGUCAUAAUUAUGCAGAAUUUUCACAAAGUUUAAUGCACAGAGAAAGCAUAUCAUUUCAGUUACUGAUACAUCUUAACACUACUUUCUUUUAAAACAGACAUUUAACAUACACAAGUUAUAGUAGCAGUAUGGGCUUCUCCUCCCAUUGGCAAUUAAAUGCUUUUAUUUUCUUCUGAAAAGAUGAUGUGGACCAACAGGUAUCAGACUUGCCAACAAGGUCGGUAGACUCUUCCCAGCAUACAUCUGAGCACUGAAGGAAGAAGAAAGUUUAAAUUGUUUAAAGGACUAUAAUUAUCACACAAAAUUUAUUAAGAAAAAAAGAAUGGAUCUAGUAUAACUAAUUCUGAGUAAACCAAAAUGAUAAUAAUUAAUUGUUGCUAUUUAAUCCCACAUUUUUGGCAGGUGUAAUUGAGCCAUGGUCUUAUUUGAUUUUGUUAUGAUUGCAUCCAAAUUCACUUUAACUCAGAGUUCUGUUUAAUGGUGGUAGGAUGUAAGAAUUGAAUUUUGAAAAGACUACUCACUGUCAAAAUCUCUCCUUCCUAUAGGAAAUUUAGCUGAGUUUUCUUCAUCCCCAAUUUCUCUCUUUUCUUGUGUUGAUUCAGUAUUCUGAACUCCAUUCUCAGCUGGGAAAGCUACAGAUCCUUUUAGUGCAAGAUAAGGUUUUAUAGCCAGAUUCAGUGGCAGACCAUGAUUUAAGAAAUUAUGUUUGGAGCCUGUGUUCUGUAAAGAGAAGGUUGAUUUGGUUUUUAGCUAUCGUAUUCGGAGUGGAACUAUAAUACAAUUGUAUAAUAUUCUUGUUGAUCAAUUCAAAGUUACUCUGCACUGUUUUUGACUUUUUAAAAAUACCUUAGAUGCAAAUUUAUAGGAGAAAAAACACUUUCAGAUAAGAGGUGUUUGCUGGGAUGGAAGAACUACCUGGCAUGUAAGAAAUAUCGUCAGUCGUCCUAAUGCAUAUUGUGACUGUUUGCAUAUACUUCUGUUUAUAAAAGUAUCAGUUUUACUUUUCAGAGGAUUUGUAAGAAUCAUUUAAAUUUUCAUUGAAAUAAACGACAAGUCACAUUGCCACUUA